GUCAUUUCUUUCCUCCAGCGUCCCCGCCCCUUCUCCUCCGGCCGCCACCAGUUUCGCUUGGCCAGUUGCGUUCGUGCGGCGACGUCCACGCAUUUUCUGACGUAGCGAGCGACGGCGGGGAGCCGAGCGGAAGUCCAGCACUAUUGCCGCUAGAGGAGGGGAGGGGUGAGAAGCAUAAGUGGCACCGGAAGUGGAAUUAAUCCGCCUACCUCUCCUGCGCCUGCGAAACAGAAAAGACAAGGCGCCUGUCGGGCGGGGUGUGGCUUCGGGUGGCGGAGAACGCUGCGAUUGGCCCUCGGCUGUGGCGACAGCGACGAUUGGUCCCUGCGUGCAGAGCGCGAGGUCCCCCCUAUUGGAAGUAAAGGGGAACAUAGAACUGAAGAGACCUCUGAUUAAGGCCCCUUCCCAGCUGCCUCUCUCAGGAAGCAGACUCAAGAGGAGGCCUGACCAGAUGGAAGAUGGCCUGGAGCCUGAGAAGAAACGGACAAGAGGCCUGGGUGCAACGACCAAAAUUACCACAUCCCACCCAAGAGUUCCAUCCCUCACUACAGUGCCACAGACACAAGGCCAGACCACAGCUCAAAAAGUUUCCAAGAAGACAGGACCCCGGUGUUCCACAGCUAUUGCCACAGGGUUGAAGAACCAGAAGCCAGUUCCUGCUGUUCCUGUCCAGAAGUCUGGCACAUCAGGUGUUCCUCCCAUGGCAGGAGGGAAGAAACCCAGCAAACGUCCAGCCUGGGACUUAAAGGGUCAGUUAUGUGACCUAAAUGCAGAACUAAAACGGUGCCGUGAGAGGACUCAAACGUUGGACCAAGAGAACCAGCAGCUUCAGGACCAGCUCAGAGAUGCCCAGCAGCAGGUCAAGGCCCUGGGGACAGAGCGCACAACACUGGAGGGGCAUUUAGCCAAGGUACAGGCCCAGGCUGAGCAGGGCCAACAGGAGCUGAAGAACUUGCGUGCUUGUGUCCUGGAGCUGGAAGAGCGGCUGAGCACGCAGGAGGGCUUGGUGCAAGAGCUUCAGAAAAAACAGGUGGAAUUGCAGGAAGAACGGAGGGGACUGAUGUCCCAACUAGAGGAGAAGGAGAGGAGGCUGCAGACAUCAGAAGCAGCCCUGUCAAGCAGCCAAGCAGAGGUGGCAUCUCUGCGGCAGGAGACUGUGGCCCAGGCAGCCUUACUGACUGAGCGGGAAGAACGUCUUCAUGGGCUAGAAAUGGAGCGCCGGCGACUGCACAACCAGCUGCAGGAACUCAAGGGCAACAUCCGUGUAUUCUGCCGGGUCCGCCCUGUCCUGCCGGGGGAGCCCACUCCACCCCCUGGCCUCCUCCUGUUUCCCUCUGGCCCUGGUGGGCCCUCUGAUCCUCCAACCCGCCUUAGCCUCUCCCGGUCUGACGAGCGGCGUGGGACCCUGAGUGGGGCACCAGCUCCCCCAACUCGCCAUGAUUUUUCCUUUGACCGGGUAUUCCCACCAGGAAGUGGACAGGAUGAAGUGUUUGAAGAGAUUGCCAUGCUUGUCCAGUCAGCCCUGGAUGGCUAUCCAGUAUGCAUCUUUGCCUAUGGCCAGACAGGCAGUGGCAAGACCUUCACAAUGGAGGGUGGGCCUGGGGGAGACCCCCAGUUGGAGGGGCUGAUCCCUCGGGCCCUGCGGCACCUCUUCUCUGUGGCUCAGGAGCUGAGUGGUCAGGGCUGGACCUACAGCUUUGUAGCAAGCUACGUAGAGAUCUACAAUGAGACUGUCCGGGACCUGCUGGCCACUGGAACCCGGAAGGGUCAAGGGGGCGAGUGUGAGAUUCGCCGUGCAGGGCCAGGGAGUGAGGAGCUCACUGUCACCAAUGCUCGAUAUGUCCCUGUCUCCUGUGAGAAAGAAGUGGACGCCCUGCUUCAUCUGGCCCGCCAGAAUCGGGCUGUGGCCCGCACAGCCCAGAAUGAACGGUCAUCACGCAGCCACAGUGUAUUCCAGCUACAGAUUUCUGGGGAGCACUCCAGCCGAGGCCUGCAGUGUGGGGCCCCCCUCAGUCUUGUGGACCUGGCCGGGAGUGAGCGACUUGACCCCGGCUUAGCCCUCGGCCCCGGGGAGCGGGAACGCCUUCGGGAAACACAGGCCAUUAACAGCAGCCUGUCCACGCUGGGGCUGGUUAUCAUGGCCCUGAGCAACAAGGAGUCCCACGUGCCUUACCGGAACAGCAAACUGACCUACCUGCUGCAGAACUCUCUGGGUGGUAGUGCUAAGAUGCUCAUGUUUGUGAACAUUUCUCCACUGGAAGAGAACGUCUCCGAGUCCCUCAACUCUCUACGCUUUGCCUCCAAGGUGAACCAGUGUGUUAUUGGUACUGCUCAGGCCAACAGGAAGUGAAGACGGAUCCAGAUCUGUGUGUGUGUGUGUGUGUGUGUGUGUGUGUGUGUGUGUGUGUGUGUGUCCCUAUGUCUAUGUAUCGGGUGAGGGGUGGGAGGGUUGCUGGAGGGUGCUUUAUUGGGUGGAGGGCACCAUGUCCCAGGGCUAUCAAAUAAAGAAUAGUUUGGUUUUUUUUUUAAAUAAAGGUUUUAUUAGCAUUUGCCCAA